ACUUCCGGUCGCGCCAGCCGCCCGUUGCCAGUUCUGCGCGUGUGAGUCUCUUUCGCCUUGCUCCGGGCUUUCUUCGCUCGCAGCGCGGCAGGGUUAUCACCAGAUCUGGGCUUUCCCCUUCUUGCCGUCAGGUGCUACGGCCACGUGGCCCGCGGCUUCCCGCUCGCGCAGUCUGGCAGCCCGGAGCCUUCCGCGGUCCCCCGCCCGCCCGGGGCCCAACGACGCCCUACUGGGCGAGCACGAUUUCCGAGGACAGGGGGUCCGGGCCCAGCGCUUUCGAUUCUCGGAGGAGCCGGGUCCGGGGGCCGACGGGGCUGUCCUGGAGGUCCACGUCCCGCAGGUGCGUGCAGCAGCACCCGCCAGGAGGCGCCUGAGGUCAGGAGCGGAUGUCGGCUGACUUGGCUGGGUUCCUGAGGGACCGGGGGUGCGGACGCUCAGCUGCGCAGCUUCCUGCUUUAGGUUGACCCCCGGAGCAAAAACGUCGGAUAUGAAGCCCUUCGGUGCAUUAAAUGUCUCUCAGUAAGAAUUUUGGAGACCCUGCCAAGAAGUGACCCUGGUCACUAUGUUGGUCAGGCUGGUCUCGAACUGUAAGCUUAAGUGAUCCUCCUGCCUCGGCCUCCCAAAGUGCUAGGAUUACAGGCAUGAGCCACUGCGCCGGGCCGGCUUUCUCCACAUCGAAUCUUUCCUGCCAGGUCCUGCAUCUCCAGUAUGGAAUGUAUGUUUGGCCCUGUGCUGUGGUCCUGGCCCAGUACCUUUGGUUUCACAGAAGAUCUCUGCCAGGCAAGGCCAUCUUAGAGAUUGGAGCUGGAGUGAGCCUUCCAGGAAUUUUGGCUGCCAAAUGUGGUGCAGAAGUAAUACUGUCAGACAGCUCAGAACUGCCUCACUGUCUGGAAGUCUGUCGGCAAAGCUGCCAAAUGAAUAACCUGCCACAUCUGCAGGUGGUAGGACUAACAUGGGGUCAUAUAUCUUGGGAUCUUCUGGCUCUACCACCACAAGAUAUUAUCCUUGCAUCUGAUGUGUUCUUUGAACCAGAAGAUUUUGAAGACAUUUUGGCUACAAUAUAUUUUUUGAUGCACAAGAAUCCCAAGGUCCAAUUGUGGUCUACUUAUCAAGUUAGGAGUGCUGACUGGUCACUUGAAGCUUUACUCUACAAAUGGGAUAUGAAAUGUGUCCACAUUCCUCUUGAGUCUUUUGAUGCAGACAAAGAAGAUAUAGCAGAAUCUACCCUUCCAGGAAGACAUACAGUUGAAAUGCUGGUCAUUUCCUUUGCAAAGGACAGUCUCUGAAUUAUACCUACAACCUGUUCUGGGACAGUAUCAAUACUGAUGAGCAACCUGGCACACAAACUAUGAGCAGACCACUUCAGCUUGAGAAUGCAGUGGGUCUGAAGAUGGUCAAGUCUGUUUGCCUUAGAUUUUGAUGUCACCUAGACAACACUUAAACUCAUAUGAAACAAAAAUUAAAAUACGUAUUACAAGUA